UGACAACCACGAACUUGAGUGUGUGGUCCUUGCCCAGGAUCUCCUCGUUGCAUAAAAUGUCCAGCUGGGGGAUAAGGAGGUUUGAUUAGCAGCGGAGAGGUGCUCAACCCACACUGACAUGGCCACCUUGAUGCUGGCCCCAUCACACCCUGUCUACCACACCUGCCGUACUGAGCAACGGGAAGAGGUGGUUUGCAGCCCCAUGAGCAGCCCUGACAGCUCCGGAAUCGGGCACCCUGGUUCCCCAGGUGGCACAGUCUCCUGCGGCUGCCGUGGAAAUUAUCACGAGGUGGUGUCUUCAAACAAUAGAAAUGUACUCAGUUCCAGAGUCCAUAACAGCCACACUCCCUCUGCAGGCUCCAGGGGAGAAGCACAGUCCAUUCCGUGCUGCUGCCACAGAACACCACACACUGGGUGAUUUAUGAAGAACAAAUUGAUUUCGGCACAGUUCUGGGAGCUGGGACAUUCAAGGUCACCACGUUGCCACCUGUGAAGGCCUUCUGCUGCAUCCUCAUGUUGGGGAAGAUCAGAAGUGAGAACACAUGCUGGCCAGUCCUUUCACAGCAGCAUCAAUCCGUGCAUGGGGCAGGGCCCUCGGCCUGAGCGCCUCCCCCAGGCCCUAACUCCCAGCACUGCCCUGCUGGGGAUGGAAUUUCCAACAUGAAUCUGGGGGAUGCUUUCGGACCACAGCCGGGGAGCCUGCCCUGGCUUCCAGCUGCUGGUGGCCCAGGGGCUCCCUGGCUUGCCUCGAGGCUGCCUCCCUCCAGCCUCCAGUCCGUCCUCUGCUCUGUCCUCACCAGGGCCUCCUGUCUCGAGUCUUCCUCCGCCUCACUUGUGUCAUGGGAUUUAGGCUCCACCCAGAUAUUCCAGAAUUAUUUCAUCCCAAAAUCCUUUAUUUAAUUAUAUCUACAAAGAUCCUUUUCCAAACAAGAUCCCAUUUGCAGGCUCUGGGGGUUAGGAUGUGGCUUAUCUUCUGGGGCCACCACUGAGUCCACUGCUGCUACAGACAGCAUCUCAAGUCUGUCCACUUCUCCACCCUGACCGCCCCCACCACAGUCCGCCUCUCCUGCAACUCCUGGCGCUGGCCUCUCCUGCGUCCAUUUCUGCACAGCCUGAGCGAUUUUCAAAAACGACACCAGACCCAUGCUCCUGCCCACAGCCGCCAGCGCCUUCUGUCUCCAUGCAAAGCUGGACCCUGCUGGCGCCUGCAUCCCCAUGGUGUCACUGCCUUGGGGGCUCACAGGGACCCACACUGGCAUGUUCAUGGUGCGCCCGCUGCCAAGGCCGCCUCAUGCCAGCACUCCUUCGUCUCCUUACACACCACAGCCUGGAAGGGUCCUCCCUCUCUGCAUCCGCCCAUGUCUCCCCUUGUGAAAUUAAAGCACAGAAUUUCUCGUUUUGAGGAAAACCUUUAUCCUAUUUUAAAACAGUCUCAUCAUCCCCGCCCUAGUUCUCUCUUCCACUCACAGUAGCAUUCCACGUUCCCUGUCUCUGGGCAUCCUACAACCCUUAGGGCUGUCUCCUAUCCCGCUCCCCGGUGAAGCAGGCAAAACGGAUUUUUUUCUGGUUAAAAUCUCCAAAAUUGUUAAAAACAAAACAAAACUAAGCAAAGAAUCUUGGAGUUACCUUUAGAAAUAAGAGAGGACUUGUUAUGGUUUCUACUUAGGGAUCAACUGUUACCUCGUUAAAGGAUGAAAGGUUGAGUUUUUUGGCGAUGAACUUCUUCAGAUGCAAGACGGUCGCCUGGGCUGAGCAGCGGAUCCACUUCCGCUUCAGCCCGCGCAGUUUGCUGCUGUUACACUCCAGGCAGAUGCUCACCUGCGGGAAAGGACGCUGGUGAGAGCGCAGCAGGAGGGUUCCCCCGGACGGUUCUGGAGGCUUCCUUAGACAUAUUUCACUAAUUCCUCAAUCUAGGACUGCUGACCUUUUUGAGAUCAGACAUCUGCUUUGACUUCAACACUGCAGAAAAAGAAUCUUACAUACCUUAUCUGAAAACCUGUUUAUCGUCUGCUUGCCAUUUUGUGAACUAUAACCUCACCCUGUUAAUUCUGUGUUAUUAACAUAAUAGUUGAGAGUUAAUCCCACAGUUACUUAUCCAUCGCAGGCACUGGGUUCUUGGUCUCCAGCUAAGCCUGUCCGGACAAACAUGGCGCAAAGGGGAGUGGGCGGCCCCGUGUCUGCGAAUGCACUCGGGGAGACAGCAGCGACUGCAGGAAGACAGUAGGGAGAAGCCUUGAGCAGGGCCACAGGCGGAAGGUCACAGCUGCCUUCCAGGUGACCAGCAGUUUGGCCGCAGGAUAAAAAGUGACUGUUAAGGGGACUGUGGAGUCCCAGCAGCCACGGGCUCCCUGCCCGGUGCGAAAAGGAAUCUGCCCAGGACGAGGCUUCACCCAAGGGCCCGGCCGGCUUGGCCCCCAAGAUGUGCCUGACAAGGAAGGGCGACGCUCACGGCAAACGCUUCUACAGGUGGAGCCGCAACAAACGGCACAGUUAGGGCCUAAAAAUGCAGUGGAAGAAUGGACAGGGGGUUAACUGAAACAUGUAUGUCUAAAAUUACAAAAGAUACAAAAGGGAGGACACCAGGGGUACAGACGGGCAAGUAUUGAAGGUAAUCAGAUACAAUUUCUAAAAAUAAAAACACUCACGGAAACUAACAUCUCAGUGGAUGGCUGAACCACAGAUUCUUCUCAGCCGAGGACAGAUUAAUGUCCUAAAAAAAAAUUCACUUGAGGAAGUUACCCAUCAGGAGUAGAGAUAAACACACCAAUUCAAACAAUAAAAGGAAGGCUAAGAGAAAGGGGAGAAGACGGGAGCCCCAAAGGGAAGAACAGAAAGGAAAGGAAGUGUUAAGAAACAGUGACUAAGGAUCUCCCACAACAGUGAAGGGCAGUCCUCAGAUUCAGGAAGCAAAAGAAUCCAAAAUACAAGAAAUACCCACUCCGACACGGUGCAGUCACUGAGCACAGCCCAUUAAAGGCCCCGCAAGAGCCACUGGGGAGAUAAGUGGAUUCUGUGCAAAAAGCAAGAGACAUCCUUGCUCCGGGGUGGGAUGGAGCGAGGCCGCCUGCAAGCAUCACAGGAGAGGGACAAUGUGAGCGGGAAGAAGAUCCGGGAGUCUGGAGAGAGAACUCGGGAGAGAGGCCGUGGGGAGAAAGACCCGGAGUCCGGAAGGAGAAGAACUCGGGAGAGGGGCCGCGCGGGGAGAAAGACCCGGAGUCCGGAAGGAGAACAACUCGGGAGAGGGGCCGCGCGGGGAGAAAGACCCGGAGUCCGGAAGGAGAACAACUCGGGAGAGGGGCCGCGCGGGGAGAAAGACCCGGAGUCCGGAAGGAGAAGAACUCGGGAGAGGGGCCGCGCGGGGAGAAAGACCCAGAGUCCGGAAGGAGAAGAACUCGGGAGAGGGGCCGCGCGGGGAGAAAGACCCGGAGUCCGGAAGGAGAAGAACUCGGGAGAGGGGCCGCGCGGGGAGAAAGACCCGGAGUCCGGAAGGAGAAGAACUCGGGAGAGGGGCCGCGCGGGGAGAAAGACCCGGAGUCCGGAAGGAGAACAACUCGGGAGAGGGGCCGCGCGGGGAGAAAGACCCGGAGUCCGGAAGGAGAAGAACUCGGGAGAGGGGCCGCGCGGGGAGAAAGACCCGGAGUCCGGAAGGAGAAGAACUCGGGAGAGGGGCCGCGCGGGGAGAAAGACCCGGAGUCCGGAAGGAGAACAACUCGGGAGAGGGGCCGCGCGGGGAGAAAGACCCGGAGUCCGGAAGGAGAACAACUCGGGAGAGGGGCCGCGCGGGGAGAAAGACCCGGAGUCCGGAGCGAGAAGAGCUCGGGAGAGGGGCCGCGCGGGGAGAAAGACCCGGAGUCCGGAAGGAGAACAACUCGGGAGAGGGGCCGCGCGGGGAGAAAGACCCGGAGUCCGGAAGGAGAAGAACUCGGGAGAGGGGCCGCGCGGGGAGAAAGACCCGGAGUCCGGAAGGAGAAGAACUCGGGAGAGGGGCCGCGCGGGGAGAAAGACCCGGAGUCCGGAAGGAGAACAACUCGGGAGAGGGGCCGCGCGGGGAGAAAGACCCGGAGUCCGGAAGGAGAACAACUCGGGAGAGGGGCCGCGCGGGGAGAAAGACCCGGAGUCCGGAGCGAGAAGAGCUCGGGAGAGGGGCCGCGCGGGGAGAAAGACCCGGAGUCCGGAAGGAGAACAACUCGGGAGAGGGGCCGCGCGGGGAGAAAGACCCGGAGUCCGGAAGGAGAAGAACUCGGGAGAGGGGCCGCGCGGGGAGAAAGACCCGGAGUCCGGAGCAAGAAGAGCUCGGGAGAGGGGCCGCGCGGGGAGAAAGACCCGGAGUCCGGAGCAAGAAGAGCUCGGGAGAGGGGCCGCGAGGGGAGAAAGACCCGGAGUCCGGAAGGAGAAGAACUCGGGAGAGGGGCCGCGCGGGGAGAAAGACCUGGAGUCCGGAAGGAGAAGAACUCGGGAGAGGGGCCGCGCGGGGAGAAAGAACUGGAGUCGGGAUGGAGAAGAACUCGGGGGAGGGGCCGUGCGGGGAAAGACCCGGAGUCUGGAGGGAGAACUCGGGAGAGGGGCCGCGUGGGGAGAAAGACCCAGAGUCCGGAGCGAGAAGAGCUCGGGAGAGGGGCCGCACGGGAAGAAAGACCCGGAGUCCGGAAGGAGAAGAACUCGGGAGAGGGGCCGCGCGGGGAGAAAGACCCGGAGUCCGGAAGGAGAAGAACUCCGGAGAGGGGCCUCGAGGGGAGAAAGACCUGGAGUCCGGAGCGAGAAGAACUCGGGAGAGGGGCCGCGCGGGGAGAAAGACCUGGAGUUUGGCGGAAGAAGUGAGAAGCAGGGAGAAAGGGGGUGCCCGGUGAGAGCCGCGGUGGGGGUGCUUGUGCAGGGAGGGGCACAGACUUACAGUGACUUUGGACUUUUUUUUUUUUUUUUUUUUUUUUUUUGAGACAGAGUCUCCCUCUGUAGCCAGGCUGGAUGCCGUGGCACGAUCUCGGCUCACUGCAACCUCCGCCUCCUGGGUUCAAGCGAUUCCGCUGCCUCAGCCUCCCGAGUAGCUGGGACUACAGGCGCGCACCAUCAUGCCCGGCUAAUUUUUUUGUAUUUUAGUAGAGACGGGGUUUCACCAAGUUGGCCAGAAUGGUCUUGAUCUCCUGACCUCGUGAUCUGCCCACCUCGGCUUCCCAAAGUGCUAGGAUUACAGGCGUGAGCCACCGCGCCGGGCCAACUUUGGAUUUCUAAAAAUGUAAAUAGUUUAUACAUUUUGUAACCACUAGUAUAACAGAAGUAGAGCUUAUACCUUGCAAACCAGAGGAAGAAAGAAAGAGAUUAAAGAAAGUUACUAAUUCACUAGACAACAGGGAGGAAGGAAGCAUUAGGAAAAAACUGACGAAAAGAGCAAAAUAAAAAAAUAAAGCAGGAACCAACUCACAUCCUCCAUGGAAAAUCGUGGAAUGUGUAAGGUAACGUGCCAGCUAAAAAAGUUUGAUUUUUUUAAAAAACCUAGCUCUACGUUGUAAACAGUGUCACAUUUAAGACAUUUUAAGAACAGAAAUAUCACACAAGUAUUCACCAACAGAAAGCUGGCAUAGCUAGAUUAGUAUGUCAUGGGACUUUAAGAAAUAGAGCUUAAUGAGGAAGAAGCCCCCCAAAGACGAGAAACGUUUCUAUACGGGAACACAGCUGGUGACAAACGCACGCCAACAGAAUGGCCAUGGUGGGCUUCACGUCUCUAUAAGCAGCGGACGCACCCUGCCCUCAACAGGCAGCCGCCGUCUCCGACUCAGGGAACAGGUGUGCCAGCCACGCAGGCACAGGUCUGAGGCAGCGGGGUCUGCAGUGCAUGGGGCCCGCAGGGCAGCAGGAAGGGCUGCACAGAUGAACGCGGGCCUGCAUGCACCUGCGGGAAAACGCAGACACACAUGGGCGGGGGUGGGAGUGGGGGGGAUUGUGGAAGGAAAACAAGAAGAAAAUAUGUUUACGUUUGCUCAGAUUUGCAUACAUACAGGAGGUGAUCACAGUGGUUCUCUAUAGGUCACUACAGACAGCGGCAGAGAUGAGAACAAAAUUAAACCUUUUCAAUAAUACUAACCUCAGGACUGAACGAAUUACCUAUUUAAAUACACUAAGUUACAAGCAUGCUUCUAAUUUUUAGGCUUUAUUAUGGCACAGUUUACACACACCUCUUUUAUGUAUAUAAUGCAAUAAUUUUCCGUAAAUUCACAGACUUUCUCGAUCAUCGCCAUGGCAGUCUCAGAUGGUUUCCAUCACCUCAGAGCCCCCGGCAGGCCCCUCUGCGAUCUAACCCUGCUGGGGGAGCGGGGUGGGGAGUGAGUGUUUAAUGGGGGCAGAGCUUCAGUUUGGGAAGAUAAAAAGGCUCUGGAGAUGAUGGUGGUGGUGGUGGCUGUGUAACACUGGGUCUGUACCCAAGGCCACUGAACCACACACCUGAAAAUGGUUAAAAUGGCAUAUUUUAUGUGCAUGUAACACAAUUUAGAAAGCUGGUUAAAAAAAACAUGAAAAUUCUAGAAUUAUUUUAAUAAGAACCAAAUUAUGAAGCUGGAAACUAAAGGAAUGUUCAACUCUAGAGUUUAGAAAAGAGCCGGGUGCAGUGGCUUACACCUGUAAUCCCAGCACUUUGGGAGGCUGAGGCGGGUGGAUCAUUUGAGGUCAGGAGUUCGAGGCCAGACGGGCCAACAUAGUGAAACCCCGUCUGUAAUAAAAAUACAAAAAUUAGCUGGGCAUGGUGGUGCGUGCCUGUAAUCCCAGCUACUCAGGAGGCGGAGGUGGGAGACUCACUUCAACCAGGGAGGUAGAGGUUGCAGUGAGCCGAGAUUGCACCCCCACACUCCAGCCUGGGCGACAGAGUAUAAGACUACAUCUCAAAAAAAAAAAAGCCAAGUGCGGCGGUGGCUCACGUCUGUAAUCCCAGCAUUUUGGGAGGCUGAGGCGGGUGAAUCACCUGAGGUUAAGAGUUCAAGACCAGCCUGAUCAACAUGGAGAAACCCCGUCUCUACUAAAAAUACAAAAAAUUAGCUGGGUAUGGUGGCAUGUGCCUAUAAUCCCAGCUACUCUGUAAGGCUGAGACAGAAGAAUCGCUUGAACCCGGGAGGUGGAGGUUGCGGUGAGCCAAGAUCAGGCCUUGCACUCCAGCCUGGGCAAGAGGGAAACUCCAUCUCCAAAAAAAAAAAAAAAAAAAAAAAAAAAAGGACAAUUCUGAAGAAGAAAAAUGAGGAGGGGUAUGUACUCUCCCAGAAGACCACAACUUAAUGGUAAAAUAAAUCAUUGCAAUUCAGUAAGUUCCUUGUUGUUUUGGCACAAUGGGAGACAAGAGACCAGCGGAACAGAGCAGAGAGCCCAGGGGGACCUGAGAGUGUGGAAACUUGGCAAAGUUGAACUCCACCUUGUCCAUUCUACACACAAGGUCAACUGCAGGGGCUUACAACCCAACUAAAAAGCAAACCUUUAAAAUAUUUUACAAGACAAUGUAAGAGAAUGUAUUUAUGACCUUAGAAUGGGGAAACAUUUUUAAGAUUCAGAAGAAAAUACCGAUACAUUUAAUUAUGUCAAAUUUUAAAACUGUGGAUGAUGAUAGGUCGAAGAAAGCCGACAGCCGCAGAAGGAAAGACGAUCCCUGCAGUGAGCGUGGGGCGGCGAGGGAGGAGGUAGCCCUGCAGCUCACAUAAGGAAAAGUCAGUCUUCCCAGGACAGAGAUGGGCAAAGAACAAGUAAGCAACUCACACGCAGAGGAGCCCAGAGACGUGCGAUGAGUCGCUGGACACCCCACACACAGGAGACUGGAAUCAGAAAUAACACAGAUACCGUGGAACACACCUGCCCAGGGGGACAAGUGCAAUGUCUUAGAAGAGUGAUGGGCUGGUCACCACCUAAAAGUCUCCAGUAUUAGAUGGGAAAUUAAGUGUAAAAAAGUCACAGCGUAACAACACGUGCCACGCACACAACGCCGUGUGCUCUGCGACACCACGCGGGCCUGUGUGCACACAGCAGUCACCAUCAAGCGGGUACGUUACACACCUCGAAAUGCAACUCUGAUUGUAAAGAGGGCACUGCAGAAAGACCUGUCGCUGUCUAUGGCUACACAUCGGCCUGCCUGGGAACACUGAGCUCCUUGUCCACCUGGAAGUGAAAAAGAGCCCAAGAUCUGCCAUCUGCAUCUGGAUCACCAGCGAAUCCUGCAGGCUCCCUCCCUUUUAAAUAUGCCCCAAACCCAGUGCUGCACCCGCACCGCCACCUGCCUGGGCCUCUGGCUCAGACGCCUGCCUGGUCUCCGCAUGGCCACCCUGGCCGUGCAGGCAGCUCACUGCAGAGCAGCUGCGCUAAGUGGCAACCCUCUGGGGAUAAAGCCACGCCAGGCUGCAUCCCACAGCACACCCCGAUCUCACAUCCCAACUGCCUCAUCUCCCUCCUCUGGGUGAACAGCAAGUUCUCGCCACAGGCCCCCAAGGUCCCCAACCUCACCUCCAGCCUUACCCGUUCACUCUGCCCCGGACUCACCACCCACGGCACGUGGGGCAGCCUGGCACCAGGUCCCAGCUCACUACCUCCUGCCUCACCUCUACAGUCCAGGAGAGGCUCUUUCUACCCUCCGCCCCUUCUACCUCCAGGGGCUCUGGCCUGGAUGGGUGGGCUCUCCGCUCCCCACCAGCCAACCCUCACCACGCCGGCUGCGAGGCCCUUGCAGGCAGAGCCCACUUCCAGCAGGCGUGCAGCAGGAGCAGGUGACCGGCUCUCGGGUGUGAAGUCCCAAGAGCACAGCGCGUGCCCGAGGGUGCGGACAGGAGCCAGUGGGCCAGGGAGGCACAACUCGGAGGAGUGAAAACAAACCACAUUUCCAGCUCCAGACACAAGAGCCAUUGGAGCCUCUGGAGGGCGGCAGGGACCCCACACCAGAACCCCCAGCCUGCUCAGGGUAUAGGAGCCAUUUCCCCUGUUUCUGGUGCUGGGACAUCACACCCACCAAGUCAACAGGCCCGGUAAGGGUUUCCUAACUCUGCACGAGCGAAGAUGAGCAGAGACCACACCAGCCCUGCAGUCCCACUGGGUCUGUGGGUGCCAGGACCACCAAAGACGGAGGCGACUCCUGCCAGGACCCAGAACGCCCCUGAAGUCCACUGGGCAGCUGCUCGCUCCAAGGGAAGCUGAAUGUAGGGUUCGUAGAAGGUCAGAGUCUCGCUCUUGUUACCCAGGCUGGAGUGCAGUGCCUCGAUCUCAGCUCACUGCAAGUUCAAGCGAUUCUCAUGCCUCAGCCUCCGAGUAGCUGGGAUUACAGGCACCCACCACCAUGCCCGGCUAAUUUUUUGUAUUUUAGUAGAGACGGGGUUUCACCUUGUUGCCCAGGCUGGUCUCGCACUCCUGAGCUUAGGCAAUCUGCCCGCCUCAGCCUCCCAAAGUACUGGGAUUACAGGCGUGAGCCACCGUGCCUGGUCCAGUCUUCUUUUUUUUUUUUUUGAGACCGGACUCUCGCUCUGUCGCCCAGGCUGGAGUGCAGUGGCGUGAUCUCGGCUCACUGCAAGCUCUGCCUCCCGGGUUUACGCCAUUAUCCUGCCUCAGCCUCCGAGUACAGGUGCCCACGACCACGCCCAGCUAAUUUUUUGUAUUUUUAGUAGAGAUGGGGUUUCACUGUGCUAGCCAGGAUGGUCUUGAUCUCCUGACCUUGUGAUCCGCCUGCCUCGGCCUCCCAAUAUGCUGGGAUUACGGGCGUGAGCCACCGCACCCGGCCAAGAGUCUUCUUAAACAUUAAGUUCUAGGCCAGGUACAGUGGCUCACACCUGUGGUCCCUACUCGGGAGGCUGAGUUGGGAGAAGCACUUGAGCCCAAGAGGUCGAGGCUGCAGGGAGCUGAGAUUGCACCACUAUACUCCAGCCUAGGCAAGAAAGUAAGAUCCUGUCUCAGAAAAAUAAAAAAGCUCUAAAGUUCUGUUCUAACUUCCUUGCCAUUUGCUCCGGGGCUUGUCAGCUCUGGGAGAGAAGGUGCCCAUGCCCUCUCCUGGGCCACCUGGCAGCUCAGGUGUGUGAGCCAUCAGCACCCAGAGGGGCCUCCAGUGAGGGCCGGGAUCUGUCUCCCACUAUCCAGGUAAUGGAGCUAAUCUCAAACACAAACCUUUGUGGUUCGACAGAGGACAAAGCCUACUGAAGUGAGAGAAGAGUUUCAUCAGGGACGUGUUCAGAAGAGCCCUGGACAGACGGGCACCAGGAGGGCACUGGCAAUCCCGAGGCUCUGAAAACGAAGAUGGGCGGAGGCCGAGUGUUUGGAUCUGACAGGGGCCUGAAGGCGGCGGGAAUCUCUGGGGUUGCCCUGGCGGGGUCACAGCCACGCGCAGGCCCCUCCCGUCUGCCCAGCCUCAGUCUGGUGGGAAGACCCCGGGGGCCUGGAACCGGAGGAGGCUGCACACACAGGGGUCGAAGUCCAUGUAGAGCCCCUGUAUCCCCAAGACUGCAUGGCCCCCCACCCCCGAGUCCCAGCGGACACUCAGGACCCCAGCUCAGGGCAGCAGGCCCGUCCCCCACCUCACUCCUUAUCCACAAACCCCACCCUUGCCCGCCCGGUCCCCGGAGGCCUCAGGAUGCCCACGCAAAGCCAGGCUCUGGAAGCAGCAGCUGGGGGAAAAGAGCGGAACAGCUGUGGCCGUGCAUCCAUGAAACCCGCCGGCUGCUCCCAAAGAAGUCAGGCUCCAGAAAGGAGAGUUCUGGAAUUAAACAGACCGAUGGCUUAUACUUAAAAAAAGAUGAGAGCAAAAAACAGCUGUGAAGCAAAUGAGUCACCUGAGGCUAACCAAGAGGCUUCUGGCUGUGAAAGGAAUGGGGUCACACAGAGAAGGUGGCAGAUGCAGGGACUGCGGGAGGCAGAACUGAGAGGAGAAAGAACGACCAGGGACCUCAGGAGGGAACAGCAAGGGCAGUGGAAGAGGCGGCUUCGCCAGUUUCCAAACUCCCAAGGUCAAGUGUGGGAAACGCCAUUCACCUGUGCAGGGGGCACCAUCUUCCAGGAGGAUCCCCAUCCCCUCCCUCGGAAAACAGAAAGAAAGGCCCCGUCAAGUAUUUUUGGUUUAGAAGACAUCGUUGUGAGUAAAUAAACCCGACACGCUUUUGCGUUGCUCAGCGAUGACUAAACUUGCCUCUCUCAGGAAGAUUCAGAGGAGCCACCAGUCCCAGGAGGCCUGUGCCUUGAGGCUGAGUGCCCACCAGUGGGGGUGGCAGCGAGGGGGCCUGCGCCCGUCAGAUGAUGGAGAAGAGGUCGGCUGUGAAGCCAGCGCGGCCGGCUGAUGCCACCCUGAGCCUCGGCUGCUCUGAGUUGGCUGCUGAACAAACCUAGAGCUGGAGCCCAGCCAGGGGUGGGAGGGCCAGAGCCUCCAGGCACAGGCACAGCAUCCACAGCUUCAUGCCCUUUGGAGGGGCCACCGGGGGAGGGCACAAGGCUGAGAGCAGAAACAUGGGCCUGGGUGGCAGGUGCUUCCCUCAUAUGUUUUUUUUUUUUUAAUGCUUAGUAUUAAAAGCACAGAAUUUAAUCAGUUCAUCCGAGUGACUGAGGAGGGCUUAAGAGUUAAGAGAAGAAACGACUGUCUCUGGUGUGAGGGGGACAACACACAGCCCGUGACCGGCAGGAGCUCAGGGGCCACCGCACUGGGCUCAGAAGUGACGUGCGGACGUGGCGAAGCACAAAUCCAAACACACCAGGAAGACACCAGAAACGGCCACAAAACCCAUGCAACCUCCCGUUAAGCCUAAAUAACUAUAACGUCGCAUCAAAACUUCAGUAAGAUGAAGAAGCGAUUCCUAGAAUAAAAUUAGUGUGAAAUAAAAUUUUAAAAUUACCCAAAACAAUCUGGAACAAACCCUCGGAUGACUUCCCAAGUUUUGGAAGACGGAGAUCAGGAACUCAUCACGAAGUUAUAGACGCGGAUAAUCCCACAAACGGACACGGAAUCCAAGUUUAAGGGCAGCCACAAGAAGAACAGAAAGAGAAUGCAAAAUUCCCAAACCAUUAGAGCAGAGAAAGAAGACACCAAAACCGGAUCCAAGCCCUCAUGGAGAGGGGAAAAAAUGUAUUCUCACAACAAAGACAACGGGUUAAACUCUCCUAUCAAAGAGAACCUGAGAUGUGUGCAAAAAAGCAAAGCAAAGGCCUCCGUAACACAGCUGAAACAAAUGACAGGGAGGGUGGAAGCAGAGACCAACAGCAACUGUAGCGAUGUUAGUACAAGAGAAUCGGGGGUUAGAGCGAAAACACACUGAACAGGAAAAAAGAAAAAAAAAGAAUCCACACUGGCAAAAGGUGCAAGUCAUCAAAACUACGUAAGAACCAUCAGCCUGCAUAGCCAGCAGCACGGCUCCUAAGCAACACCGCGAGGUUACAGAGACACGGAGAAAACAAGAAUCCACAAGAAAAACGACCGGACUUGGAUGUCGGAGUUCACAAUCUCCCAGGCUGCCUGCUUGUUUCUCAUUCAUUCAACUUAACACCUCAAAGUGCCUCACAAAUAGGAAAUCAUUUAAUCUUCAUAAAAACCUCGAGGCAAUCUCACCACCACCUCACGCCACAGACAGAGAAACUGAGGCAGAGGUAGGUCACUUGUGAAGGGCCACACCCUGGCUAAAGGCAGAGCAGGACGUGGGCAACUGGCCCCCGGGGUCCGCUUGUUUACCCACCACACCAACCAGCAAACUCAGCCAAAGGAAAAUCACCCCAGGACCCCUGGAAAAUCUGCACCCAAGUGAACAAGCAAGAAGAUCUCAAUCCCCCAAGGCAGAGAUCCGUGUAGACAACACUCCCUGACCGCCCGGGAAGGAGACUAGAAAGAGGAGUGGAUGGAACCCAAAAAGGCCACGUUACUCAAAUGUUUCAGAACAAACUUCUCGAUUAAAAAGGAACUCUGAUGAAAUUACAGCUUCUUUAGAAAUGAAUGCCAGUGAAAAUAUUAUUCAUCAAAGUCCGCAGGGAGCAGCCAGGAGCACACAGGAAACACAGCCGGAAAUGCGCUUACAAAGACUUGGCGGGCACGUGGGCUCACGCCUGGAAUCCUGGCACUUUGGGAGACUGAGGCAGGUGGACUGCUUCAGCCCAGGAGUUCAGACCGGCCUAGGCAACACAGCAAGACUCCAUCCAUCUCUACAAAAAAUUAAAAAAGUUAACUGGUGUGAUCUGCCAACAGUGUCUGCUACUCUGGAGGCUUGGGCAGGAGCCCAGGAGGCAGAGGGUACAGGGAGCUGUGAUUGCACCAUUGCACUCCAGGUUGGGUGAGAGAGCCAGAUCCCGUCUCAAAGAAUAACAAAAGACUUUUAACUCAAGAUGUCAGAAAAAAAAAAGUUUUAAGAAAAUUCAGCAAGGCUGGGUGCAGUGACUCACACUUUGGGAAGCCGAGGCAGGUGGAUCACGAGGUCAGGAGUUCAAGACCAGCCUGGCCAACAUGGUGAAACCCCAUUUCUACUAAAAAUAUAAAAAUUAGCCGGGUGUGGUGGGGUGUGCCUGUAAUCCCAGCUACUUAGGAGGCUGAAGCAGGAGAAUCGCUUGAACCCAGGAGGCAGAGGUUGCAGUGAGCCAAGAUUGUGCCACUGCACUCCACACUCCAGCCUGGCGACAAAGUGAGACUGUCUCAAAAAAAAAAAAAAAAAAAAAAAAGGAAAGAAAAUUCAGCAGGGCAUGGUGGCUCAUGCCUGUAAUUCUAGAACUUUGGGAGGCUGAGGUGGGUGGAUCACCCGAGGUCAAGAGUUCAAGAUCAGCCUGACCAACAUGGAGAAACCCCAUCUCUACUAAAAAUUCAAAAUUAGCCAGGCGUGGUGGCGCAUGCCUGUAAUCCCAGCUACUUGGGAGGCUGAGGCAGGAUAAUCGCUUGAACAUGGGAGGCAGAGGUUGCAGUGAGCCGAGAUCGUGCCAUUGCACUCCAGCCUGGGCAACAAGAGCAAAACUUCAUCUCAAAAAAGAAAAAAACAAAAUUCAAUAUUUGAUCAAUUUAAAAAAAUUGGCCCUUUUGAAAGCAACAAAUAAAUCUUUAGCACGUCAAGGAUCAAAAGAAAAGGUAAAUAUUAGUAAAAGUAAACACUGAUAUAAAUUUAAAACUGCAAAACAGAGAUUAAACUGGAGGAGGACAUCACACACAGCUUUACAUCGAUCCAUGGAAAACCACACCAGAGUAAAGGGGAGCAGCAGCCUGCACCCCUCUGGAACACCAGCCCACCCAGCAGACCCCAAAACUGAAUUUCCACGAGAUCCCAGGGGGUUCCUCACCACUGGGGAACUGCUGUAAGGACAAGUACCUAACAAAGGCCAACCAGGAAAGACCCAGGGGCCUCCGCGCAGACGAGACCAACACCAGAGACAGAAAAACAGCGUGGUUCCAGGAGAGCCGCCAAGCCACCAACAGAGGAAGCACCAGGUACGUCAACAUCGGAAACCAGGCAUGGCAGUGAAACCGGGGUCAUGAAAGAAGAAGGUGAUUUCCUCGCUUCCUGCCCCUCCGGACCCCUUCUCUGAACUGGCCGCUCUUCUCUACUGACCCACAAGGCAACGCCAUCACAUCCCACGUUGGACACACGUGUCUAUUUCUGUAAUGCUCACUGAACGUUUUAAACAACGUGUAAAUGUAAACUAAAAAAUUAAGGUUCCGUUACUUGGCUGGGCGCGGUGGCUCAUGCCUGUAACCCCAGCACUUUGGGAGGCUGAGGCGGGCCAGAAGUUCGAGACCAGCCUGGCCAACGUGGUGAAACCCUGUCACUACUAAAAAUACAAAAGUUAACCAGACGGAGCGGCAGGUGCCUGUAGUCCCAGCUACUCGGGAGGCUGAGGCAGGAGAAUCGCUUGAACCCAGGAGGCAGAGGCUGCAGUGAGCCGGGAUGGUGCCACCGCAUUCCAGCCUGGCAGACAAGAGCAAAACUCCAUCUCAAAAAAAAAAAAAAGUUCUCUAGACGUGGGUAUGGAAUUUCAUCAAAUUCUUUUACUGCAUCUCUGUGACCGUGUAGUUUUUCUGUCUUCAUCUGGUAAUACAGUAAAUGACACACGAAGAGGCCCUCGA